AAGAGGCCUCAAAGAAAGAGCUGCGGUGCAGGAAUUCGUGUGCCGGAUUUGGUUAGCUGAGCCCACCGAGAGGGGCAGGGCUGAUCCAGCUGUGGGUCUCUUGGUUCCCUCUUUCAGCGCCUGCAGGAUGAAAGCUCUCUGUCUCCUCCUCCUCCCUGUCCUGGGGCUGUUGGUGUCUAGCAAGACCCUGUGCUCCAUGGAAGAAGCCAUCAAUGAGAGGAUCCAGGAGGUCGCCGGCUCCCUAAUAUUUAGGGCAAUAAGCAGCAUUGGCCUGGAGUGCCAGAGCGUCACCUCCAGGGGGGACCUGGCUACUUGCCCCCGAGGCUUCGCCGUCACCGGCUGCACUUGUGGCUCCGCCUGUGGCUCGUGGGAUGUGCGCGCCGAGACCACAUGUCACUGCCAGUGCGCGGGCAUGGACUGGACCGGAGCGCGCUGCUGUCGUGUGCAGCCCUGAGGUCGCGCGCAGCGCGUGCACAGCGCGGGCGGAGGCGGCUCCAGGUCCGGAGGGGUUGCGGGGGAGCUGGAAAUAAACCUGGAGAUGAUGAUGAUGAUGAUGAUGA